ACUUCCAAGACAGACACGGAAGUGCUGGGAGGCGCCGGGAGCCCGUUCGGUUGCGGGUGUCUCUGGCCCUGCGGUCAGCCCUGGGAACGUCCCGGAGAGCUAGAUUCCUAGAGGCCCGAUUCCGCUAGCCCGGAACAGACAAAGCCAGCGCUCCCGCCCGCUCCCCGACUUAGGAUCCGAUGCCGGCAGCGUCCUGGGGCCCCCGUAGCGGGGCUGGACCAUGAGCCUGCUGGACGGCCUCGCUUCCUCGCCGCGGGCUCCGCUGCAGUCCAGCAAGGCCAGGAUGAAAAAGCUCCCGAAGAAGAGCCAGAAUGAGAAGUACCGGCUGAAGUACCUGCGGCUGCGCAAAGCGGCCAAGGCCACGGUGUUUGUGAGUCUGACCCACGUUCAGCCGGUCCCCUCCUGGAGACUCCCUCACAAAAUCUUUCCCCAAGCUGUUCCCCCUUCCCAGUGUGACAGUAUUAAUACAGUGUUGGCUUUUCCGUAUACGUUACUACUUGUUAGCCUUGUGUCCUUGGACAAAUUACGUAAUUUCUCUGUGUCCUCAUCUGUAAAUGAGCUAGUAACUGUCUUGCAGAAUAAUGAAUAUUAAAUGAGUAAAGAAAAGUGCUUGGUGCGUAAAAGACAUACCAAUAAAUUUUAGUCAUCGUUGUUACUGCAGGACUCUAGGAAAUGUGUUUGAUUCUCGAGAUACAGCCCUGAGAAUUAGGCAUUAUUUGUAAAAUGAGAACACUGAAGCCCAGAGAGAUGAUUUGCCCAAGGGUACUGUGUCAGAGCCCUGACUCCAACUUAGAUAAACCUGAUUCCGUUUUAUGACUUCCAGUACACAGACUAUUUUCUGAGCACCUCAAAUCCCCAUAACUGACCCUUUGCCCAAAGAGGUACAUGAAACUGUCAGUAAUUUCCCCCCUCUAACCUUUGAGUGUUCCAAGUGUUUCUUCCUUUCUUUUAUUGUAGAAGCACUGGAUUUAUUGAGUGAAUAAACUUAAUAUAGCUUGCCAGCCAUAACUUUAUAUUAGAAUAGUUUGGCUUGCCUCAGUGCUUGGAAAUAGGGGUGGAGUCCUCAAAUGUCCCCCCACAUCCAAGUCAACAGUUCAUCUCUUCUCUCUACCAAAAGCUUGAACGUCUCUCAGCAUUUUUGGAAGCAUAAGGAAAGGUUCAGAAAUUAGAAUACACAUUCCAAAAGCACUUAUUCAGCACUUGCUAUGUGUAUUGCUUGCUAUUUGCACUGGAGAGAAACAAGAAAAGUAAAACUAAGAGAACUUAGCAUCUGAUUGACUGUUCCCUUUCUUUUAUCCCCUAUACGUCAAAGGUACCUAAAGCUUGGAAUUUAUGUUAUUUCAAGGAUAUUGGUUCCAUCAAAUACAUAAUGAAGAUUUUGUGAAGAAAAAGCGAUGUUGUUUUGAACAUUGAGAGUUUGAAGUUCCACCUAUGGGGGCAUUCAGAUUCAGCAUUCCCUUCAGGAUUGGUGCUUGGGAGAUAGAUUGAGUCAUCAUUUACAAAAAAAAAAAAAAAAAAAAGAAAAAAGAUAAUACUUGAAUUCGUAUAAGUAGAUUGUGAAGUUUAAGAAUUUUACACACUAAAUUUGAUUUUGUUCUGUCCAGUUUUUCUCUAUUUGGGUUAGACUGGCUUUGUAAGUUUUUCAAGAGUUGAGGCACUUGGGAAUAGACAGUUUUCAUAUUUAUAGUAUUUAAUUUAAGCAUAUAAGGAUUUAAGCAGUAUGCCUUUUUCUUUGCCAAAGGCUAUACUAAUUAGGGUGACCAUUAAUCUUGGCUUGCCCAGGACAGUCCUGGUUCACCGUAUUGUUCUGGCAUAAGCAUUAAUAGUACCCCCUUUUCACUCAAAGAUGUCCCGGAUUGGAUAAUAAAUUACAUAGCUAUACCCUGUCCAUAGUAGAACCUGACUACCUUUAUCUAUGGAUUUAUUUAUAGUUUGUCACACGGUCGAAUAGCUCCUUCUUCUCAGUAAUACAAGCUUUUUUGGUUUGAAAUAUGGAUCCUCUUCCCAGCAUAAUAAUGUGAUUUUUUUAUUCAUUUUAUGUUAUUAUAUUCACAUUUUUACUUAAAGGAAAAUGCUGCUAUUUGUGAUGAAAUUGCUCGUCUUGAGGAAAAAUUUCUUAAAGCAAAAGAAGAAAGAAGGUGAGCUGGCUUCAUUUUGUGUUCAGCAUCACCUUUUUGGUGAUUGAUUUGGUGAUUGAUAAUGGUGUUACUGCUCUGGAGACUUUUUUUCCCAGUGGGAUUGAUGCGUAUCGCACAGCCCCUUGGCCACUUGAUCAAGCACAGAGAAACUUACAGCCUGAGGCAUUGGUGCCUGCACACCCAAGUUAUGUUGGGCCAUGGCGAUGAGACAGCUCCUCUACUCAUCUUUCUGAAAAAGCCAUCUUGCCACAUCUAAUAAAUAAUCUUACUAAGAUUAUUUAAUCUUAUGGCCCAAUUAUAAAAGCCAAGUGAUAAAAGCAACUGCCUCUCGUUCUACAAAUAUUUAUUCUGUACGUACUAUUCUGUGCAAAGCACAAUGGGUAUAUAUACAUGUGUAAAUAAUGUGCCUUUCAGAAGCCUAACACCGUCCAACAUCAAGGUAGAGGAACCGUCCAGAUGCAAGAGAUAAGCUACAGUUCUUAUCCUUGGCCUCUUGAAGUAUUGAUUAUCCUCCAGGGCUUUAUGAUUCAUAGGGCCUAAUAAGAACCUUUCUUUUAUGAGUAUAGUAAUCUUUGUAUAUAAUUCUGGCUUUUCCCAGUACUUGAGUAAAAUACUGAAUUGAGACAAUACGGAAGUUCAUUUCUCUGCUCCUUUCCUUCCUGAUCUCAGGUACUUGCUAAAGAAGCUCCUCCAGCUUCAGGCUCUAACUGAAGGGGAAGUACAGGCUGCAGCUCCUUCCCACAGUUCCAGUUUGCCCCUGACUUAUGGUGUGGCCAGCUCUGUGGGAACUAUACAGGGAGCUGGGCCUAUUUCAGGGCCCAGCACUGGGGCUGAGGAACCAUUUGGGAAGAAAACUAAGAAGGAGAAAAAAGAAAAAGGCAAAGAGAACAACAAACUGGAAGAUCAUCACCGACCGACCUGGCUUUCAUGAUGAGAGUGCCAUCUACCCCGUGGGCUAUUGCAGUACUCGAAUAUAUGCCAGCAUGAAGUGCCCAGACCAGAAGUGUCUAUAUACCUGUCAGAUCAAGGAUGGUGGUGUGCAGCCUCAGUUUGAAAUUGUUCCUGAAGAUGACCCCCAGAAUGCCAUUGUCAGCUCUUCUGCAGAUGCUUGUCAUGCAGAACUGCUCAGGACUAUAAGCACUACUAUGGGGAAACUAAUGCCUAACCUGCUUCCAGCUGGAGCUGACUUUUUUGGAUUUUCUCAUCCAGCCAUCCACAACCUGAUCCAGAGCUGUCCAGGAGCUCGAAAAUGCAUCAAUUACCAGUGGGUGAAAUUUGAUGUGUGCAAACCUGGAGAUGGGCAGCUACCUGAGGGGCUGCCGGAGAAUGAUGCAGCUAUGAGCUUUGAAGCCUUUCAGAGACAGAUCUUUGAUGAAGAUCAGAAUGAUCCCCUUCUGCCAGGAUCCUUGGACCUCCCAGAGCUUCAGCCUGCAGCCUUUGUGUCUUCUUACCAGCCCAUGUACCUGACACAUGAACCCUUGGUAGAUACUCACCUGCAGCACUUGAAGUCUCCAUCACAGGGUAGCCCAAUUCAGUCUUCAGAUUGAACAAGAAGGGAUCAGAUGCCACAUCGUUUUUGUCGUGAUUAAUUUAACUUAAACUAAAAUUUUGGGUAUAUGAAAGAAGGCAGCAAUUCAGAAGUAAAGAAGAUACUAACGUAUUUCAUCAUGGAAGGUCCUGUGGUGAUGGUUUUCCCUGGGAAAACCUUCAGCUGCUUUAUUUUUAGUAAUAAAUUUCUCUUGUCAAUUCUGUUUACUUUCAUCUUGUAAUCGGGAUGUAAUCUUUUUUGCUUAGCUCUGCCUGAGGUAAAGUAAACUUCAGCCUCUUAUAAACAAGAGUGAUAGAGAGCUGCAGGCUGCUACAACAAAUACCAUAGACAGGUUGGUUUAUAAAUAACAUGAAUUUAUUUCUCACAGUUCUGGAUGCUGGGAAGUCCAAGUUCAAGGAGCGCAGAUUCAAUGUCUGGUGAGGGCCCACUUCCUAGUUCUUAGACAGCUGUCUUCCUGCAGUGUCCUCACGUGGUAGAAGAGGAAGGCAGCUCUCCGGGGUCCCUUUUAUAAGAUCACUAAGCCGGUUCAUGAGAGGUCUGCUCUCAUGACCUAAUCACCUCCCAAAGGCCCCACCUCCCAAUACCAUCACAUUAGGGGUUAGGAUUUAACAUGAAUUUUGGGGACAUAUAAACAUUAAGUCUGUAGUAGCAGCAGCUGACUAACGAGGGAGAUAGGGAGAUUCUGACAAACUUCUACUCUUGAUUGUGAUCCUAAUUCAAGGAAUAUCAAGUCCCAGCCCCUGCAACCCAGGCUGCUGCUUAAUUUUCAUGUCAGUAUCAUCAAAAUCCAAUGUUCUGCUUAAACUCAAGAUGGAAAGUCCAGUCCAAGGUACACUGUUCAUCUUUUUCUUCACAUUUUGCACAUCCUUCAAGGGGAUCUUUAACCUCUUUAACCUUUGUAUUGCACCUCAGAUAAUGUGCUUUUUAGCUCAGUACACUGAAACCAUAUGAUAACACAAAUUCACAUAUAAUUGGGGGUUAGUCCCAUACUCUAUAACAGACUUAGUCCUGUCUUUUCAUUAGCCAUGUAAUAAUAUAACUCCAUGUUCCAUGCAACUGGAUUUUUGGACCCUGUUAAUAGCAUUAAGGUAGAGGUUUACUCUAUCACCUAACACCUCAACACUACCUGUGGGAUGCCUUAGUUACCCAGCAGCAGGUUACCAAGGGCUGUCUGGAAAGGGAGGGACAAAAGGACCCAGAAGUAGAAGAAUGGGGAUGGAGUGGUGAGAAUUGAAUGGUUAAUGCACUGCCAUUCAUAAUUGCCAAUUGAGGACAACACAAAUGGGAUUGGUACUUUAUAGUAAUAAAUCUGACCAGCAGAGGGAGGGAUCAGGCAGCAGUGUUUAGAGCACACCACACUGGCCACUGUAAACUGAGAAGCUAAGUUAACUGGUAUUUUAUGAUUUUGAGUAUAGUCUUUUUAUAAGUUGUAUACACUUUACAAUGUAAAAGAAACAAACUUUGUAUAAUAGCAAAUCGGGAAGGGGACUGCUUAAAAUGUUAAUGCAGUGUUUUUCUUUUUUUCUCUGCAUAAAUGGCUUGAGCAUACUGGCAUUUACACAGAAAUGAUAUAUGCUGCUUUUAUCAUAUAACAAAUAUUUUCCCACUAUUACAGCCUGAGUAAUACCCGUAUUAAAAGAGCCUCAUUUUAGAAAGACAUUUAAAAUUUUUGGAACAUACCACAUGUAGAAAGGUUGAACUGGUUUUUCAGCUAUAAUGCAUAUACAACUAUAGUGUGUACGUAUACCACAUAUACAUAUACUUGUAUGAAGAUAUGUGUAAAAUGUUUUUACUAUGGAUCAUGGAUUUAAGAAACUUGAAAAGCUGGGCACGGUGGCUCACGCCUGUAAUCCCAGCACUUUGGGAGGCUGAGGCGGGUGGAUCAAGAGGUCAGGAGAUCGAGACCAUCCUGGCUAAGUCGGUCUCUAAUAAAAAUACAAAAAAUUAGCCAGGCGUGGUGGCACGCGCCUGUAGUCCCAGCUACUCGGGAGGCUGAGGCAGGAAGAAUCGCUUGAACCCGGGAGGCAGAGGUUGCAGUGAGCCGAGACCGCGCCACUGCACUCCAGCCUGGGCAACAGAGCAAAACUCCAACUCAAAAACAAAAACAAAAACACCUUGAAAAACACUGCCUUAGUAUACUUAAACUAUCUUUUCAUCUAUCAGAUUGUUAAGGAUUUUUUUUAAAUUUGACAACAUCCAGUGUCAAUGAGGGUGAGGGCAAAAAAAGGACUACCUUGGUGAGAAUGUAAGUUGUUUAAUCCUUUGGGAGGGUUAAGCUGUAGAUAUCUAAAUUUUAAAUAUAUAUUUAUCCUCUUCCAUGUUAAGAACCCUAAGAAAUAACUGGACGAGUGUGGUAUGAUGUUUGCAUGUGAUAUUCAUUACAGUAUUAUUUUAAUAGUAGAAAAUUGUUAAAAAUCUAUAUGUCCAUUAAUAGGAAAUUGGUUAAAUAAAAUGAGGCUUCCACAAACUGAAACACUCUAAAUCUAUAUUCUAUUAUUUACAUAAGAAAAUUAUUUUGGUAAAGUAAGUAAGUCAAAAACACAGAUUACAAAAUAAUAUGUACUGUAUAAAAUUAUAUAACUCAAGUCAAGUGAAUGGUUCAGCAAAAUAGUGUUUCUCUGAAUGAUGAAUUUGGGGGUGAUUUUUACUUGCUUAUACUUUAGUGUCCAAAUUUUCUACAGUGACUAUAAAUUUCAUUUUAAAACUAAAAAGUUCUUACAUUUGGGGAAAUGCAGUGAAUUCCCACAUCAUGUUUUAAAUUACUCAGCCACUAAAAAUGAAUGUGCAUGGCGUCAUUAACAUAAUCAUUGCCUGAACCGUAUUUUUCACACUAUGUACUCUAGGUUCCUGGAGGUGAAAGGAAUCUGGACUUAGAGUUCUUGGCUACCUCUGGCUGCCCCCGAAUUAGAACAGCCCAUGGGGGUAUGUGUAUUGGGAGUGGAGGAGUGGACGGGUAGAUUGACUUUUUCUCAGGCAUCAAUCUGUUACAAGGUUCAUGGUUUCUAUGGGGCCAGAUGCAUGAGAGGUCAAAGCAUGGGCAAUAGGGGUUAACUGAACGAGUUGAAUGCUAGGAAGUCCUCAGGGGAGCCAACGUUCCUUGUAAAGUGUGUAGAUUUUUUGUUUUUUAACUAAAUAAAAUCUUGGCACUGACAAAGUUAUUCCUGCUGUUUGGAGCUACACCAGAACCCCUUGGAACUCUACAGAGGGGUAGAACUAAAGCAAAAACCAUCAUUCACCCUACAGAGUAUUAUAAAUUUCAUUUUCACACAGUAAAAAGUUCCUAAAUUGGGGGAAACAUAGUGAAUUCCACAUAAUGUUUUAAAUUAUUCAGCCACUAAAAAUAAAUUUACAUAUGAUUUCAUUAAUAUAUUCACUAUCUAAACCAUAUUUUUUACACUACGUAAAAUACAUUGUAUAUGUACAGUGAGUGAUGCUUUUUGCUUUAGUUCUCAUUUUUCACAUUAAGGGGAGGAAAGCUACCCAUAGAUAGUAUUCUUACUCCUUUUCACAUGCUUCAAGGACAGUUUGCAAGUGGAUAUAAAUACAUACACAUCACUAGUGAUUAUGCUUUUAUUUAUUUCCAACUUCUUAUAGGUAACAUAAUUUUCAGACAAUGUUAGCUGUUUUUAAUCCAUCAGUAAACUGCAUUAAGAUUCUUAAUAAACAAACACUGAAGGCCUCUUUCA